AGUUACCAGCUUUGGCUGCUCGCGCCUCCCCAACUCGGGUAAAGCUCCUCGGCCUCGGCGUGCUGCGCCUCCGCGGCUGCCCUGCGCCAGGUGAGGGCUCGCGGCUCCCGGCUGCGGCUCCCGGCGCGUGGUGGCGGGCUCGGGGCGUGCGUCGCGGAGAGGACGGGGCCGGCGGGCGGUUGGCGCUCCGUUCGGUGCGGGGAGGGGCGUCACGCCGGGCGCUGCGCGGCCUCGGCGGGCGGCGGCAGCGGCGGCCACGGCCGCCGGGCUCUCGGGUUGUCUGUCCCCAGUUGGAGCCGGCCGGUGUCCCGGCGGAGAGACGGGCAGUCGGGUUCCCUGGCCUCGGGGCCACCCCGGCUGGGGCGGCUGGGGCAGAGGGACGAUGUCUACUCGCGCCCCGAUGCCCGCCGCCCAUUCUCGGGAGGAUCCGCCCGCGGUGACUGCUGAGAGGGAGUCGCUGUUGGCCGCGGCGAACCGGCCGGCCGAGCAGCCGCCCCCGCCCGAAUGUGAGGGCAAAGAGGCGGCGAGGGAGGAGAGGGCCGCGGCCGCCACUAGCGCUGGGGCGCGGGGAGAGCCGUCGCCGGCGCUGGUGCUGGGACGCAGCGUGCCCCAGGCGGCUGUCCCCGUGAGGCCCCUGGCGCUGCACCUGGCGCACAAGGCGCGUGGGCCCGGGGGCCCUUUCGGCGGGGAGCCGCCACCGCCACCGCCGCCGCCGUCGCCGUUGCCGCCGUUGCUGCGGGAUCCGCCGGCCGAGGACGCCCGGGAAGAGGUGGCAGCUGGCCCUGCGGAAAAGCGGCAGCCGCCGCUGCUGCCGCCUAAGGGAAAUCCCUGGACCAAAAAGCCUCCCCAGCACCUGUCCCCAGACACGACAGGUCCGCCACCGCCCCCGCUGGAAACCCUGGAGGCAGAAUUCGGUUCCCUCAAAAUUAUAAAGGCAGGAAAGCUCAAGACAAAGAAAUCCAACAAGGCUAGUGAUUUCAGUGAUAUGGAGAAUUGGCCAACACCAAGUGAAUUAGUGAACACUGGAUUUCAGAGCGUCCUCAGCCAAGGAAAUAAAAAGCCACAAAAUAGAAAAGAAAAAGAAGAGAAGGUUGAAAAGAGAAGUAACAGUGACAGCAAAGAAAACCGGGAAACAAAAUUAAAUGGUCCUGGUGAAAACGUCAGUGAGGAUGAGGCUCAGUCAAGUAAUCAACGUAAGAGAGCUAAUAAGCACAAGUGGGUACCACUCCACUUAGAUGUUGUAAGAUCAGAGAGUCAAGAAAGACCUGGAUCCCGGAACAGCUCAAGAUGUCAACCUGAAGCAAAUAAACCAACACAUAACAAUAGGAGAAAUGAUACACGAAGUUGGAAGCGAGAUAGAGAAAAAAGGGAUGAUCAAGAUGACGUUUCCAGUGUGAGAAGUGAGGGUGGUAAUAUCCGAGGUUCCUUUAGAGGUCGAGGAAGAGGCCGAGGACGGGGAAGAGGACGAGGCAGAGGAAAUCCUCGAUUGAACUUUGAUUAUUCAUAUGGUUAUCAAGAACAUGGUGAAAGGACUGAUCAACCAUUUCAAACAGAACUUAAUACCAGUAUGAUGUAUUACUAUGAUGAUGGUACAGGUGUACAGGUGUAUCCUGUGGAAGAAGCAUUGCUUAAAGAGUAUAUUAAGCGUCAAAUUGAAUAUUACUUCAGUGUAGAAAAUUUGGAACGAGACUUCUUUCUUCGGGGAAAGAUGGAUGAACAAGGUUUCUUGCCUAUUUCCCUGAUUGCUGGUUUUCAGCGUGUUCAGGCUCUCACUACAAACCUUAAUCUCAUCUUAGAGGCACUGAAGGAUAGCACAGAAGUAGAAAUUGUGGAUGAGAAAAUGAGAAAAAAGAUAGAACCAGAAAAAUGGCCAAUUCCAGGCCCUCCUCCACGCAGUGUGCCACCAACAGACUUCUCUCAACUGAUUGAUUGUCCAGAGUUUGUACCAGGCCAAGCCUUUUGCUCACAUACAGAGUCUGCCCCAAAUUCUCCAAGAAUUGGAAGCCCAUUGAGCCCAAAGAAAAACAGUGAAACAAGUAUUCUUCAAGCAAUGUCUAGAGGUUUGUCUACCAGUUUGCCUGACUUGGACUCAGAACCUUGGAUAGAAGUUAAAAAAAGACAUCAGCCAGCCCCAGUGAAAUUGAGGGAAUCAGUGUCUGUCCCUGAAGGGUCAUUAAAUCAGCUAUGUUCUUCAGAAGAACCAGAACAAGAAGAACUUGAUUUUUUGUUUGAUGAAGAGAUUGAACAAAUAGGACGAAAAAACACAUUUACUGAUUGGUCUGAUAAUGAUUCAGAUUAUGAAAUUGAUGACCAAGACUUAAACAAGAUUUUGAUUGUAACUCAGACACCACCUUAUGUGAAAAAACAUCCUGGAGGAGAUCGAACAGGCACCCACAUGUCUCGGGCAAAAAUCACAUCUGAACUUGCUAAAGUUAUCAAUGAUGGCUUAUACUAUUAUGAACAGGAUCUAUGGAUGGAAGAAGAUGAAAACAAACACACAGCCAUAAAGCAAGAAGUUGAGAACUUUAAGAAGCUAAAUCUCAUUAGUAAAGAGCAGUUUGAAAACCUAACACCUGAACUUCCUUUUGAGCCAAACCAAGAAGUUCCUGUAGCACCUUCACAGUCCAGGCAAGAGGAAUGCUGGCGUCAUAAAAUGAGUUGGAGGUGUUCAAGGAGUGCUUCACAUUCCCAAGAAAGAAUAAUCAUUCUGGUAACAGUGAAGAAAAUGGAUUGGGAGAGGAAAUGGCAAAUGUAUUUGACUGAUGAAUUAGCUCAGAAGUUAUUUGAUGUUUCAGAAAUAACUUCAGCAGCAAUGGUUCAUUCGUUGCCUACAGCAGUUCCAGAAUCUCCUAGAAUUCAUCCUACAAGAACACCCAAAACACCUCGAACACCUAGGUUACAAGAUCCUAACAAAACACCAAGAUUUUAUCCUGUUGUUAAAGAACCAAAAGCCAUUGAUGUAAAGAGUCCAAGAAAGAGAAAAACAAGGCAUAGCACAAAUCCCCCUCUAGAGUGUCAUGUUGGUUGGGUAAUGGAUUCCAGAGACCGUGGGCCAGGAACAUCCUCUGUCAGCACUUCAAAUGCUUCACCUUCAGAAGGCGCACCACUAGCAGGAAGUUAUGGAUGUACUCCUCAUUCAUUCCCAAAGUUCCAGCAUCCUUCUCAUGAACUUUUGAAGGAAAAUGGCUUUACCCAACAAGUGUACCACAAGUAUCGUCGAAGAUGCCUAAGUGAGAGAAAACGCUUGGGAAUUGGUCAGUCCCAAGAAAUGAAUACCCUCUUUCGUUUCUGGUCCUUUUUCCUCAGAGAUCACUUCAAUAAAAAAAUGUAUGAGGAAUUUAGACAACUUGCUUGGGAAGAUGCAAAAGAAAAUUACAGGUAUGGGUUAGAAUGUCUGUUCAGGUUUUAUAGUUAUGGACUGGAAAAAAAAUUCAGGCGAGAAAUUUUUCAGGAUUUCCAAGAAGAAACCAAAAAAGACUACGAAUCUGGUCAGCUGUAUGGACUAGAAAAGUUUUGGGCUUAUUUGAAAUAUUCUCAAUCUAAGACACAGUCUAUUGACCCAAAACUUCAGGAAUACCUCUGUAGUUUUAAGAGGUUAGAAGACUUCCGUGUUGAUCCCCCUAUUAGUGAUGAAUUUGGAAGAAAAAGACAUUCCUCUACUUCUGGUGAGGAGAGUAAUCGUCAUAGACUUCCACCUAAUUCCUCUACAAAGCCACCAAAUGCUGCUAAACCUACAUCUACCAGUGAGCUUCAGGUACCAAUAAACUCUCCCAGAAGGAAUAUUUCACCGGAGUCCAGUGACAAUUCACAUUAAACAGUGCUGCCUGUGUCCUGUGGUCUCAAGAAAUGGUGAAAUGCCUGAGAAAUAGACUCUUAUGAAAGUUCUUUGUCCUUGAAGUCAACAUUUACAUCAGUAUUUAUUUGGGGAAAAUCUUCUGGUGUUUAAUUGUGAUAAUAAGAAAGAAGAAAAAGAAAGAAAAGUGGUAGCAUUUUUUCUAACAAGAUAAAUUCUAAAAAUGUUUUCCCUGAUUUCACAAACAAGGAUAGUCUUGGUGACCUUUUAUAGAGAUCUUCUAGUAAUGUAUUUUGAUCUCAGAUUUCUUUUUCAAAGCCAUGGUUUUACAAAAACAGCAUUCCUUAAAUAUAUUUAAAAAACAAUACAAGGAAUGCCUAACAUUUCAGCUCAUACUUCUUAAAGAAGAUAUAGUAUGUUGUAUUCUCUUCUUAGAGCUUUCUUAAAGAAUCCACAAUCCAAUUACCCCACUGUCAAUUCAUAUUUGAACUUACCAAAACAAAGGAGGAUUACGUAUAUGUUUUUUAAAUUCAAAAAAGAAUAUGAAAUUAUACCUUUAGUAUCCCUUUGAGACAUAUAGUUUAAAGAAAACUUUUUUUAAAACAAAAGUAGGAAUAUAUAGUAAGAUUGUAGUUACAAUGAGUAUAUGCACUUUUGAUGCUAGGUUUUGCUUUUCUCCCCCCAGUCAUAUCUCAUGAUUUCCACAGUUGUUGUAUUGGUGUGGAGUUUUCUGAAUUGGCUAUAAGCUGAUUACAUAUUAGAGGUUUAUUUUUAUGAUUCUAUAUAAACGUGCACGAGUAAUUUAAAACCUGCAUUGGGAUUGAUUGGAAUAUUGUCCUAAAUUAAUUAAAUCUUGCACUGUUUUGAAUGCAUCUGCUAUUUAUACAUCUGCAAGUGGGUAUGUCAUAAGGAGUCAGAUUAUCUUUAAUUUAAAAUGAAUACUUAGUUUUACCUUUUUGUUUAUUUUUUGUUUAAUUUUGUUUUUAUAAAUGUUUUCAAGAGUUAUAGCAAAUUGAUUUCUAAUUUUUAUUGCUAUUACAACUGAUGUAAAUGGUAGUUUCAGUUUUUGUGAGAUUUAAAAAAAUAAAGCACUUAUUCUGAAUUUUUUGAAUUGAUUUUUAAUUAUUUUUAUUUAGAAUAUAGUUGAAAAGCUGUAAUAUUCAGUUUUGCUAGUAAAAGACCAUUUUUUUGUGUGAAUGAAGUUUCAAUUAUAAACUUACAUUCACUUUAUUGAGCACUACAUAAUUUACAGAUAUUUUGUUGUAUUGGCAAAAGCAAGUGGUUUCCAUAUGCUAAAUUAAUUGUAUUUUCUUUUUGAGCAGAUUGGAUAUCUUGUUCUUAUAAAUUAUAAUAUUGAAAUACAUAUAAUCUUUGGAUGGAUGGGCUGUUAAUUUGUAAAUAGGUUUUCAUUAAGUUAUUUCUCAUGAUAAGUAAUAAUCAGCAGUUUUAUAAUAUUUACUAUUUGGAGGGUCAUUUUGAUGCUUUAAAUUGCAGAAAUAGUCAAAUUUGAAUAUUCAGAAAAUAAAUUUAUUUAGAUAUAUUGUAAAGAGGGUGCAAAACAAGCAAUGGGUUAGAAUAAUAGAUCUUCAAGUCUUUUCUUAAAUGGGGUAUGUAGUUCCAGCUUUUCAGUGAGAAAUUUCCAAACCGUGCUUAUUAGCUUUAAAUGGUCUCUUGAAAUGAUCAUAAAUUUUUCUCAGUGUCCUUUUUGUGUUGAACACAUAUAUCUGAAACCUGUAUUUAACCAGAUAUUUCUACUCAACUGAAUAUACAAGUGUAAAUUUGAUUGGAAAAUUGUAUAUUAUAAAUGAAAAUACAAUAAUCAGGAGUUUUGUGGUUUGUAUUAAUUAGUAGUUUUAUCAUAUUUUUAUUAUAAAAGUAAUACAUGUACAUUGGGAAAUUUAGAAAAGCACAAAGAAGAAAAUAAAGUACUUGUUAUAAAAAGAAGAAAAACCAAAA